UGGAUUUCAUAAGUCACAUGGCUGGAAGGUACCUGAUACAGAUUAAACACAGAAUUUAGUUAGGAUAGCAUUCUGUCUUUGAAGGCUGUGUGAUUGCAGCCCAGGCCAAGCCAGGCAGAAGUUGGGUCACUUGAGCAGGGCCCUGCAAACACACCUGAAGGAGGUGGCAUUGCUAGGACUCUACUUUUGGGGCUGAAUCAGCAGAGGCAAAAGGACUGAGUAAGUCCUUGCUGAGGAUGGCACAGCUCUCAGCUACAGAGCUAGGACCAGACCAGGCUCUGGGGUUCAUGCGGGAAUCACCAGUCUGCGCUGCUGCCUCCUCCUGUAUGCGUGUGUGUGUGCGCGCGUGUGCGUAUAUGUGUGUGCGCGCGUGUGCGUAUAUGUGUGUGCACGUGUGUUUGCGCGCGUGUGUGCGCGCUUGUGUGUAUAUGUGUGUGCGCGCGUGUGCGUAUGUGUGUGCACUGCGCGCGUGUGCGCGCUUGUGCAUAUAUGUGUGUGCACGUGUGUGCGCGCGUGUGCGUAUAUGUGUGUGCACGUGUGUGUCCCCAUGAGUCCUGUGGCACCACCGAGUUGUCAUGAAUGCUUUCGUUUAACGAGUCAGGAGCAGUUUCCCAUUUUGUAGGCUGUUUUUCUGUGACCUGGAUUUUAAUGGCUUGGUCAACAGGUGGAAAAGUAUCCACCUUUCCUUAUCAGUCUGGAGGCUGGUUGGUUUUUUCUGCGUCGCCUGCGUCACCACUUCCUGAUGUCAGCGCACGGGGCUCUGCGCCCCCCCAGGACUGGAGGCUCCGUGUAGAUGGAGACUUUUGUUUUUGUCCCAUCCUCCUGGCAUGUAGAAGGCCCUCAAAUACUUGUUGAAGAAUAAAUGGACGGGCUUUGGUAUUUUAUAACCUAGCAAUGCACCUUUUGGUUGUUUCCAGGUUUACUAUUAAAACCAACGUCUUGAUGCCCCUCUUUCUGGAUGCUUUUGGUGAUAGAGAAGCCAAAUCACGCUGGUUUUAAGCAAAAAUCAUGUAUUUGCUCCUGAAAUUUUCCUUUGAAAACUUUCUGUGUGCGGUUGUACGUCAGUAUGUGGUUUUCAGCCACACUGGGAGGCGCCUUUCUCUCUCUUUUUGUCGCUAUAGACAUUAGUGGAAAGCCACAAGUAGCGUGGGGGCUGCCUCUAGUCACGCUUCAGCUGCAAGUGCGGUGUGAGCAUCUAUUUUUACCUCACAGUCCUCGCUCUGAAAAAUUCUGACCACUUUUAUUUUUAACAUUCUGCUCUAUUAGCUGGGUGCAGGGAGGAAGGAAGCUCAAAUUAGUCAGUUUACUUUGUAUUUAUUUUUACUUGACCUUUUCACUUCCACAUUUUGAGAAGAAAAUGUGAGACUCUUUCCUCUGCAUAAUUUUCUUCCUUGAGGAGAAACCAUUUUCAGUCAUGCUUGGAAAGAGGUGGAGAUAACCUCAGGGUAGCAUGUUUAGCGUUUUCCAUUCACGAAACAAACCUUAAAAUGUUCAUCUGUUUAUUCUAUGAAAUAAUUAGUUUCUUAUUUCCCACGAAUUUGAAAACCAGUACAUUUCUGUGCCAAGUAAUGGCUGUGUUUUCUUGACCAUCCGGCAAGUCUCUACCUGGGUGUGGUGACUUGGGGACCGCGUUGUCAAAGAGCCAGUGAGGCGGGGGUGUGGAGAAUUUGUUUGCCCUUUGUUUUUCACUUACCUUUUUCUGCAGGAAUUGAACUAAACAAUUGCUACUGACAAUGAUGUAUUUUAAUUCCUAGGAGGUUAAACUCCUCACCUAGAACAGUUUGAUUAAUAAACCUAAUCUAUUUAAGCAUGUGUCAAUCCUUUUGGAAAUUGUAAUAUUCAAGGACUUGCUAGCAUUUAUGGCUCUUUAAAUAUUUCUAGUUAUAGUUGCUGUCAGGAUUCAUUUAUUUUGAUUGGGUAAUUAGUUUUUUACCAUUAUUUUAAAAACUAAUAAACAUUUUAAUCAGAUCUCAUGGACAGAAAGCCAAGAUUCUUGUGCUGCUUCCUAAAUGCAGUGGGCGCAUCUCUGUCAGUUUUUACCUGCUGGAAGGUACUCCUGAGUGCUGUGCUGAGCUCUGCCCAUCUGUCCAUCCUCUUGGGACACUCAUCCCUUUCCCAUUCUCUGCUCUGUGAGGGGAUGGUGCUAGUGAGAGCUCAGGUCGAGAGGGCUGGGGUGCUCCUUCGUCUCUCAGCUCAUCAGCAGUGACUUGGAAGACAAUCAGGGUCUACCUGUGUUGUUGAGAAGCGUUACGCAAGCAGGAAAGCGCACAAGAGGAAGGCGCAGCUGAGUGAAGCAUUGCAGAGCCCGCCAGGCUGUGCCUUCCACCCAGGCCAGCACACGGAGCGCUGCAGUCCCUGAAGGCUUCCUCAGGCUCCUCCUGUUGGCGUGGGUGCCUGCCACUGACCUCUGUGGGUGACAGGUUUGUCACUUGAGCUUGUAUCCUGCAACCUGUUUGUUUGGGCGUGCCUGUUUGUUUGUUUUUAACGUUUUAAUAAACUUUAUUUUUUAGAGCAGUUUUAUAUUUACAGCAAAAUUGAGGGACAGGUACAAAGAUUUCCCGUAUGCCCCCUGCCCCCACACAGGCACAGCCUCCCCCAUUAUCAACAUCCGUAUCCGGAGCCGUGUAUUUGUUACAGUUGAUGACCCCAUGUUGACACCUCAUUACCCAGAGUUCAUGGUUUCCAUGAGGGUGCACUCUUAGUGUUGGACGUUCUAUGGGUUUGUACACAUUUAUGACGAUAUGGAUCCAUCCUUACAGUAUGCAGAAUUGUUUCAUUGCCCUUAAAGUCCUAUGCUUAGCCUAUUUUUUAACUAUAUAAAUGCAGUCAAAGGAUGUGUUUUUGUGUGUUUUCUUUUGUUCAGUAUUACAUGUGUGAUGAGACUUGCCUGUGUUGUUGCCUGUUCGUUUUUACUGCUGUACAUAGUACUCUGCUGUUUGACCAUAUCAUAUAUUCAUUCUGCUGACGAUGGAUAGUUAGACGGUUUCCAGUUUGGGGCCAUUAUAAGCAAAACUGUUCUGACCAUACUGAUACAUGUGUUUUGGUAAAGAAGCACAGGUGUUGCUGGGGUGGAUGGGCUGGCUGUGAGCACACGCACUUCAGCGUGAGUGGGUGAUGCUGGCAUGGUGCCUGGUUGGGCACUCAACUGCCUGCUUUCACCACACUCCCCAUGUGGCAUCAACUGCUUUGGAAGUUUCUGUCUUCUUAAUUUUUACCAUUCUGGGCAGGUGUGUGUGGUAUUUUUCUGUAGUUUUGAUUCUCAUGGACCUGCUUACUAGUGAGAUUGAGCUUUUGUUACAUUUCAUGGAAUUCUGGACUCUCUGAGAUGCCUCCCAAAGUGCCCAGCUACAGCCUCUGUCAUCAGGGAAGGAGCAGGUAUGGGAAUGGUGUCUCUGCACACCUCAUGUCUUGCCUACAUCCUUCUUCAAGAAAAUACUGGUUUUCCCCCUGAAAAUGAUAGAAAUUGACUCAUCAUUUUUGAGUCUAGCUCAGGUGUCUUUUCUGGAAUUGCCUUUUUUAUUCGGUGUAAAGAGGCACAGGGACUUCAUAUCUGCUAUAGAUGAGUGAAGGUUGCCUAGACAUGCACACAAGGCCCUUGGUGGACUUCCCCUAUCCCUGGGGCUCCUCAUAACCCUUCCCUCUUCUCUUCCCUGGACUUUCUGGGCUGGGGCCAGGGCUUGGGGUCGGGGGUGAGCCUUCCUCUCGGUGUGUAUCUCUGUGUAGAGUUGCAUGGUGAGAUUCGGCUUCUGUUCUAAAUGCAGUUGGGUGGAAAUAAAGCAGGGAUGGUCCUGAGUCACCCACAUUCCUCUUGGUCAGUCUGCCCUGGUGUGAGGAGCUGGCAGCCUCUGCAGACCUUUGGUCCCACUUCCCAUUUGGGGGAUGUAGGCUUGUGUUAUAAAAUAGGUGAACAUGUGAUUUACUGAUUUACUGCUUGAACAGGGACACUUUUGAGAGUGAAAGGGCCUGCAAUUAUUAAUGACCCCAAGAUGACAUGUGAUAACGAGGAAGUUCUGGGGAGAUCAGGUCAUGAUCCCCAGAGUUAUGAUCUCAAAGAUGGAGAGUGUCAUAGGGAGGAUGCCCCUCUGUGAGUUGUGAGGGGCCACGUGUGUCCUGUGUACACAGGCCCUAAGGGGUGCUGGGGCCAUGUGGGUAGUCAUAGGAAGAUGGCUGGAGUUGGGAGGCAGAAUGUUUAAGAAGUAUUUCACUCAUUGACUAAACUUAGUUGAGUUUUAUUUGUCUGUGAAAAGGGAAAUCUACUUGCCUUGCUUGCACGCCUUUCCUAGGGAUAUUUUGGGGACUAAAAUGUGAUAGUGAAUUUUAAAAUAUUGGUUGAAAUGGCCAGGCUCGGUGGCUCACGCCUGUAAUUCCAGCACUUUGGGAGGCCGAGGUGGGUGGAUCACAAGGUCAGGAGUUCGAGACCAGCCUGGCCAACAUGGUGAAACCCCAUCUCUACUAAUAAUACAAAAAUUAGCCAGGCGUGGUGUUGCACACCUGUAGUCCCAGCUACUCGGGAGGCUGAGGCAGGAGAAUUGCUUGAACACAGGAGGUGGAGGUUGCAGUGAGCUAAGAUCGUGCCACUGUACUCCAGCCUGGGCGACAGAGCAAGACUCUGUCUCAAAAACAAAACAAAACAAAACUAUAUAUAUAUAUGUGUGUGUGUGUAUAUAUAUAUAUGUGUGUGUGUGUAUAUAUGUGUGUGUGUGUGUGUGUGUGUGUGUAUAUAUAUAUAUAUGUUGACAUGUGAGUUUUUCAGUUUACUCUGAACUCUCUCCUUGUCUGUUUUUUAAAGCAUCCUGAAAGGGAGUGUCUGUACAGCGUCACCUGUUAACAGCCACUAGGAAGCUGCCCUGAGAGUUGGACCUGGCCGAGCUCUCUGAUACUUGAGCAGCCCUGCCCAGAGGAGCCUGUGCAGCACAUGAGGGUUCUUCAGUAUUGGUCGGUGUUUCGGGAGCCCUUACAAUGAAUGAACACAGCUGCAGCCCAGUGACCCCUCUUGGACAAGUGCGGAGAUCAGUUUUAGCUCAGCUGCUUUCUGAAUGUUUCAGAUAUUUCAAACUGGAAGUCACAAGUAGCUUUUACUUUUGCAAGCAGUCUGCUGUUAUGAAUAGCACGUAUAAGAAAAUUUAUAAUUCAGUUAGUUAAAAAUAUGUUUGAGCACCUGUUAAAGCACCAGAAUUCUUUUAUAAAUUGAGGAAAGCCAUGCCAUCUAACACAUAUGUGGCAUUAAGUGUUCUUUUAAUAAAUAUUAUGCUUAGUAGACAUACUCUACAUACCAAUCAGAGGUUGCCAUCCUAAACCAAAACUACAUAUCCAGCACAUUCUGAUAUUAGGCGGUGGCUUACACCAGGGAAGGCUUGGAGGUUGUUUUGGCUCCUACCCUUUAAAAGGCUUACCAGCUUUUAGAUGGAGUCAUAGAUAAGACAUGGAUAGUAACAGAAAGGAAGCAUGGCUUAUCAGCUGUGUCAAGUCAGGACACAUGUAUCCCCAUUCACAUUGCUGAACUCAGGAAGAUAUCCAAGCACCAUUGUGACAUACUUGUCCACAGAGACCGCAGAUAACCCCAGCACCCUCUCAGAGUGGUGCCUUGGUGUUUUUGUUCAUAAAGCCUUGAUGCUCAGGCCCAUCCGUCAUCCCGGGCAGGUGCGUAGCCUGUGUGGUGGAUGCCAGGGUCAGGGGAGGGCUUUGCUUUUGCAGAGUCUCGAGGCUUAGGCUGAAUGUGUUUUUAAAGGUCCGACUAUACUGAAACAAACAUUAAAAAAUAUUCAACAUCACUUAAUUUUUAUUGCUUAAGAGCUUAUCUGGCUCUCCCAUUGGCUCAGUAAUUUGGUUGCUAUUAAUAACGUUGUUGAGGUUGUCAUCGUCACCUUAACAUUGUCAUCAUCACCUCCAGUAAUAGCUAACAUUUAUUGAGUUCUUCCUCCAUGCAGGAACUGUGCUGAGUUCUUUUUCUGCAUUAUUUUAUUCAGCCUUUGCUGCAGCCAUCUGCAGCAGGCACUGUUACUAACCUUCUCCUGCCAGAGGGAACGCUUGAGAUGCUGCAGGGUGACAGUAGCCUCAGAGCCAGGGGGCUGCAUUGCUGGAUCUUCAAGCAGGCAAACUGCCAACUCUGUGUUCAUAAUCCUGGUCAUGGGCUCGCACUGACCUGUAGAGAGCUGGAUAUGGGGAAUGGAUUGGAGAGCUUUUAUUUGAAACAACAGCAAAGUGGCAUGAUCUUUUGGGAAUACACUUUUUCAAGUCAUGUAUCCACUCACAGACAGGCUUUGUGAGCCUCUUGCUUUGUUAAGGGCCCAGGGAAGAUUUUAAGGCGACCAAACUUCCAGUGACAAACAAUAUUUGAAAUUAGUCUAUUCCUUUACCCCAGAAAUGCAGAAAUACAUGGUUUUGGAUGUUUGACCUCAUUGGUUGGUGGGCAUGAGGAGGUGGUCUGCUUUGGUGCCAGUGACCGUCUGUGAGUCACAGAGUGAGUGAAUGCUGAGCCGCUGUGAUGGGAAAGCUCUCUGCUGAGUUGGUUCAGUCUGGGUCACAGAGUGAGUGAAUGCUGGGCUGCUGUGAUGGGAAAGCUGUCUGCUGAAUUGGUUCAGCAGUGCACCUGCUUCCUCACGGGGCAUUAGCCGGUCAGGGCGAUGUCUCUGGAUCACUCAACUUGUCCCUGACAGAGCAAGGAAUAAGAAACCCAGUUAGAUUGUCUGUAUCAUCAGAUGCCAUUUACAUCCCAGUCAAAUUAGCAGCCAGAUCACUGAUUUCUUAUAGGUAUACAUCUUUUGACUUCAGCAUAAUCUCUUCCCCUUUUUCUGCAUCCUUGGGUUUUAAAGGAUGUUUACUAUGUAAAUGUUUAACAUGUUUACUAUUUAAACUUAAUAGUUGAGGUAGCUUUUAAAAUUUGUGUCCAUUAAACCCAAGGACUCUUGCAGAAGUCGUAUGGUUUUUCUUCUUUCAUCUAUAAUGCAUGUAAGGAAUUAUUCACUUGCUCUAAAGUUCAAAUGUGUGAGUUUCUGGUGCUGUUACAUAACACGUGGUAUUGUGGGUCAAGGGGAGUUAGUGUCUCACCUAAAAUCUGGGGCCAUGAUGUCACCACAUUAAAUAGUAGGGAUGCUUGCUCAUCUUUUAAGGGUAUUUCUUCCCCCUGCAAAGCAAAAUGCUGAAGAGAUACAUAUUUGUUAAUUAACUGAUUUCACCCUCGUCAUCCAUCCUCUUUCCAUAAGGAACUGUAUGUUGCAUUCUUGCUGAGUGCAGACUAAGUCCUUUGUGCAAGGUUGGGUCAUCCUGGGGUGAAAAGGUAAGUGCUUUCGGGGAUGCUGAUUAAGGUGGUAUCUGCUGUGCCUCUCUCAGUGUCCCCAGGGCGAAAUUCCUCAGGUUACAGUGGCAGGAACAGCUGCUUGAGCUCAUUUUUGUCUUCUGAACAGGAUCAGUCUUGGAAUUGGCCUUUUCUCCAUCUUCAGCCCCAGGGUGGGGCUGGCCUGGGUAGGGCCUGCGCCUGUGCUUGCUGCGCAGCAGCACCCCUGCGUGCCUUCCCUUGCCUCGGCUGCUAAGUCUUUGGAGAAAACUCUACAUUGCCAAGCUUCUUCUGAAAGAUUUAAUUUUUUAUUUAGAAACAGUAUGCUUAUUACAGACUGUGCAGACUUUGCAGAAAUGCAAAACUAGGAAGAGACAUAUUAGUCCCUUUGCAUAGAAGCAACUUUUGUUAUUAUUUUGUAUGUUUCCUUUGUAUCUGUAUUAGUGUGUUCUCAUACUGCUAAUAAAGACAUACCAAAGACUGGGUGAUUUAUGAAGGAAAAAGGUUUAACAGACUCACAGUUCAGCAUGACUGAGAAGGCCUCAGGAAACUUACAAUCAUGGUGGAAGGGGAAGCAAACACAUCAUUCUUCACAUGGCAACAGCAAGGAGAAGUGUCCAGCAAAAUGGGGAAAAGCCCCUUACAAAGCCGUCAGAUCCCGUGAGAACUCACUCACUAUCACGAAAACAGCAUGAGGGUAACUGCCCCCAUGAUACAAUUACCUCCCACUGGGUCCCUCCCACAGCACGUGGGGAUUAUGGGAACUACAAUUGAAGAUGAGAUUUGAGUGGGGACAUGGCCAAACAAUAUCUGUGUCUUUUUUCAUGUAUAUGUUUUUUUUUUCUUUUCUCAGCAUAAUUGAUAUACUGUGGUUACUCUACCUAUUUGUGUAGGCCUCUCAGGUCAUUGAAACAAGAUGUUGUACAAAUUAGCAGAUGACACUGGCGCAUGGAGGAAUGGUUUGUAUUUUAAUUUUCACUGUAUAACAUUUUAGUAAAGCUUUUACUGGAAAUGUUUUCUACCCAUAUCCUCAGGAAACCAUGUGAAGUAGACAGCCUUGCAUUUCCUGGAUUGCUCCCUCGAAGGAUGAAGGGAGCAGUUCUAUCAGAUGCUCUUCCCAGCCUCCUUCUCCAGGGAGACCUAGCCGCUGCUGUUUUGAGUUUCCUGGGAGGACAUCCCCCAAGGACUCUCUGGCUUGUCCUUGUGAAGUUGGUUUGCUUUUUGUGCCAGCUUUUUAGGCUUACAAAAUGUUGUGUGUGUGUACAUAGGAAAAAUAUGGAAGGGUACGUACCCACUAGUUUGUGUCAGCACUGGAUUCUGGCAUAUAUAAUAGAUGAGGAGUUUCUGUUAUGUAUAUGGGAUUUCUGAGAUACACAGGGGUUUUCUGUGCACAUCUCUCUAUAACGCAGCUGUCCCGUCACAUCCUGCAUGUCAGUACAGGUAGUGCCGUUCUCUUCGUAGGACUGUGACACUUUAUCUUUGUUCUUUCACAGUUAAAAAAAAAAAAGCUUCUUUAAAAUUCUGACUUUAUAUAACUAACGCAAUGCUCAUGCUACUUCACUUGUUACAAGAACAUAUUAUUCUGUCCUAUAGAUGUACUGCAGUUAUUUAAUGGAUCAGCUAUUGAUAAGGGGGCCCUUUUAAUGUAACUAUUUUAAAAAAUGGAAGUAAUACCAGCACAUGGUAAAAAACACAUUGCAGCUCAUGAAUGGGUAUAAAUUAAGUUGGAGAUUUCCUCUUUCUCCCUCCCCACCCCAUGCCCCGUUUCCAGAGGUAAACAAUGUACAGUUUGUGUUUUCUUCUCUUAAGUUCUUCUUGUAGUCACCAUUAUAGCUUUAACUUUUCUGUUUGUGAGUUCAUGUGGAAGUCAACAGUGCCUUCACACUCUGAGUUUUGAUGAGAUUUAUAUUGACAAGGCUUAAAACAUUUGUAGUGUUUCCCAUCUAUCAUUAGGCUCCCUGUGCUUUUCCUGCAAGUGUAGUCUAAACAUUUUAAUAUAAGAAAAGUAACAUUUAUAGUAUUAUGAUAGUAUAUUUUGCCAUAGAACCAAGUGGUAUGAAAUGUAAUUCUGCCUCACCAAACCUUUGCCAAUAAAAGGAGAAUAUUCAGAUGGAACUCCCAGUUUCUCUUUAGGUGUCCGCUGUUUCUAGCUGCCUCAGUUGCCAUGGUUUCUCCUAUCCCAUGGUGUUGGUUUCUUGGAUUCUAUUUUUGUUUUGCUGGAGCACCUCCUUAAUCCACUUCCUUAUAGAAUGGAUGGCUGACAGACUUCUUAAUUCACUUCCUUAUAGAAUGGAUGGCUGACAGACUUCUUAAUUCACUUCCUUAUAGAAUGGAUGGCUGACAGACUUCUUGGGUUUUUGCACGUAAUGUUCAAACAUGCAAUUACUUUGUUCUCAUACUUAUUGAUAAUUUGGUAGGGUCUAGAAUUCUAGGAUCGUAUAAUUUUCCUUUUGAAAUCAGAAAAUAUUCUCUAUUAUUUUCCAGAGUCUAGUGUUGGUAAUGAGAAGUUGGAUAUCCGUUUGAUCCUUGUUCUACUGCAGGUAAACAUCUUCUACUCUCUCCUUCUCUCCCUCCCUGGGCUUCAUGUCCUGACGGUUUGAUUUUUCGUUACCCUAAACCCGGAUCUGCUUCUCUUCCAGCCCGCGUGCCCAUAUUGGGAUCACCCCUUAGAAAACCUCAGGCUUUCUUUGGAGAGCGAUUCUCAGGUUUCAGCCCAGGAAUAAAAGCGUUCCCUAUGGCUCCUGCUUCUUGGGAAGACCCCUCACCUCUGUUGUCUUGCUCUGCAGUUUCCUCUGCUCUCUCGCAUCAACCUGCUUUCGUCUGCCUUAUGCCCUAAAAGCCCUGGCAGGCUUUCUUGUGUUCUGCUAAAUCCCUCUGUAAAUUUUUAGCACCGUGCACUAUUAUGGUUCAUUCACCACCAAAAAGUACCUUUUCUGACAUUUUAACAGAGCUCUGGGAAGAAUGGAGAGAAGAUAUGGUGUACUUUAUCACCAUUUUUAAUUAAAAGCCCUUUUAAUUAAUUAAUUUAGAGGCAGGGUCUCGCUCUGUCACCCAGGGUGAAGUGCAGUAGUGUGAUCGUGGCUCACUGCAGCCUCCACCUUCUGGGCUCAAGCAAUACUCCUGUUAUCAGCCUCUUGAGUAGCUUGGACCACAGUCACGUGCCACAUUGACUGAUUAAUUUUUAAAUUUUUUGUAGAGGUGGGGUCUUGCCGUGUUGCCCAGACUGGUCUCGAACUCCUAGGCUCAAGCCAUCCUCCCACCUUGGCCUCCCAAAGUGCUGAGCACACCACUGUGCCUAGCCUAAAAGCCUUUUUAGAUCACUCUCAGUGGCAAAAUUAGUGCCUUGGUCACCUUUACCAGUAGCUGUUCUUGCUCUCCAGUGGAAAUAUCACUCAACAUUAUCAAAGAAUCGGGAUGAAAUUAAAUGAACCAGUUUAGGUACUUUUGAUACAGAAGUUCUUAUGAGACGUGUUGUUCUUUACUAUGUAAGAGUGUGGCCAUAAACUUAAAAAUAGCUGGGUAACUUUGUUACACUUGCCUUGAUGGUGUGUUGCAAGUUAGUUAAAUUUCAUAUACUCUUAAUCAGCACAUCACCAACAAAUAAAAUGUUACUGCUGCAUCAGAAUUUAGAGGAGGUUCUAUACAUCUGUUUCGAAAUAAAGACGGAGAUGACUUAGGGUACUUAUAAGUUGUUGAAAAAUCAUGGCUCCUGAAACUAUGAAUUGUCAUCGUGGUAUAUACCCAGACAGCCCACAUUAAACUGCUGUGAACAUGAGAAAAUGGACAUCGAAAUGAUAAAAGCAAGAGUGUUGGUAAUUGAAAUCCAUUAUAAAUAAAGCUGUCAUUGGUAACGCACGAAAUGCUGUUUCUGAGGAUGAGGACUUUGUGGCCCCCACGUGGGCGCAUUACCAAGCUUUGCAGCUCUGCACAGGAGCCUCCCUUCUUGAUACUGAACUAGACCUCUAUAAAGCCUAGUAACACCUCAGGUUUAGGUUAUAAAUCUUAAAUUUUAGUGCCCCGUAAUAAUUCACUUCGUAGGUUACCAUGGACUAGCCCUUAGUUGCACUGAGAAAAGAAAGGCUAUGAAAUUUUGUUGGUGAAGUGCCAAAGAAAGGAUUGGGUUUUGGGUCAUCUCACAGCCCAUGGUGAGGGCUGUCUUUGGCCUCUACCGCACGGACAAGUUUGCAUGUCAGAUGUUGGCACACUUGUGGGGUAUUGGGUUCUUUUGAAUAUCUGAUUAAAUCCAUUUACAUUUUCGUUAGAAAAAUUCAUCUGUGCAUAUGAACGCAUCAUUUCAUAUAUGAUUUCACACUUCUCAUUGUCUUCCUGAAGCCCAUUCGUGAACUGUCGAUUGAAUGCCUGCUCUGGAGAGGAGUGUGAAGCUGCACUUCUUCCGUCUCCUCCUGGCACUCGCUCAGGAUCCUCACAGGUGUGGAAAACACUCUAAGGAAGCCUGCGAAGGCCAGAUGUCUCCCUUUUGCCUUCUUUGGUUCUGUUCAUGAUGGCCUUAUCACGGACACACUAGGACCCUCUGAGGACACCACCCCUGCCACCGCAUUGCUCUGGGGGCAACUUCCGAGCUUAUUGUCUUCCUCCAGCAAGGGCAGGAAUGUGGAGAAGCUGUGUGUGCUGGGCCUUUACUUUCAUUAUUGGCGACAAUGUUUGUUUUCAUUUUAUCAGCUUUCUUUAUCCUCCAUUUUUUUAUCUUCCACAGGUAGUGUAUAUUUUGAGAACAGCGUGAGGUUUAUUCUACUAAUGGAAAUUUACAAAAAUACCAGUUUGAAUGAUUGAGAAAUCUAAGUUAAAGAACCCUUGAAUAGAAAUGUCGCUGUUCAGUGCGUUGAUCGAUUCUCACAUCUGAAGCCAGCUGUGUAUUCUUGAGUGGAGCCUUUCAGGCUGGCAUGGAGAGCUUAAGGGGCAACUGAAGGAGACACACUGGCCAAGCGCGGAGUUCUGCUUACUUCAGUCCUGCUGAGAUACUCUCUCAGUCCGCUCGCACCGAAGGAAGCUGCCUUGGGAUCAGAGCAGACAUAAAGCUAGAAAAAUUUCAAGACAGAAACAGUCUCCGCCAGUCAAGAAACCCUCAAAAGUAUUUUGCCAUGGAUAUAGAAGAUGAAGAAAACAUGAGUUCCAGCAGCACUGAUGUGAAGGAAAACCGCAAUCUGGACAACGUGUCCCCCAAGGAUGGCAGCACACCUGGGCCUGGCGAGGGCUCUCAGCUCUCCAAUGGGGGUGGUGGUGGCCCCGGCAGAAAGCGGCCCCUGGAGGAGGGCAGCAAUGGCCACUCCAAGUACCGCCUGAAGAAAAGGAGGAAAACACCAGGGCCCGUCCUCCCCAAGAACGCCCUGAUGCAGCUGAAUGAGAUCAAGCCUGGUUUGCAGUACACACUCCUGUCCCAGACUGGGCCCGUGCACGCGCCUUUGUUUGUCAUGUCUGUGGAGGUGAAUGGCCAGGUUUUUGAGGGCUCUGGUCCCACAAAGAAAAAGGCAAAACUCCAUGCUGCUGAGAAGGCCUUGAGGUCUUUCGUUCAGUUUCCUAAUGCCUCUGAGGCCCACCUGGCCAUGGGGAGGACCCUGUCUGUCAACACGGACUUCACAUCUGACCAGGCCGACUUCCCUGACACGCUCUUCAAUGGUUUUGAAACUCCUGACAAGGCGGAGCCUCCCUUUUACGUGGGCUCCAAUGGGGAUGACUCCUUCAGUUCCAGCGGGGACCUCAGCUUGUCUGCUUCCCCGGUGCCUGCCAGCCUAGCCCAGCCUCCUCUCCCUGUCUUACCACCAUUCCCACCCCCGAGUGGGAAGAAUCCCGUGAUGAUCUUGAACGAACUGCGCCCAGGACUCAAGUAUGACUUCCUCUCCGAGAGCGGGGAGAGCCAUGCCAAGAGCUUCGUCAUGUCUGUGGUCGUGGAUGGUCAGUUCUUUGAAGGCUCGGGGAGAAACAAGAAGCUUGCCAAGGCCCGGGCUGCGCAGUCUGCCCUGGCCGCCAUUUUUAACUUGCACUUGGAUCAGACGCCAUCUCGCCAGCCUAUUCCCAGUGAGGGUCUUCAGCUGCAUUUACCGCAGGUUUUAGCUGACGCUGUCUCACGCCUGGUCCUGGGUAAGUUUGGUGACCUGACCGACAACUUCUCCUCCCCUCACGCUCGCAGAAAAGUGCUGGCUGGAGUCGUCAUGACAACAGGCACAGAUGUUAAAGAUGCCAAGGUGAUAAGUGUUUCUACAGGAACAAAAUGUAUUAAUGGUGAAUACAUGAGUGAUCGUGGCCUUGCAUUAAAUGACUGCCAUGCAGAAAUAAUAUCUCGGAGAUCCUUGCUCAGAUUUCUUUAUACACAACUUGAGCUUUACUUAAAUAACAAAGAUGAUCAAAAAAGAUCCAUCUUUCAGAAAUCAGAGCGAGGGGGGUUUAGGCUGAAGGAGAAUGUCCAGUUUCAUCUGUACAUCAGCACCUCUCCCUGUGGAGAUGCCAGAAUCUUCUCACCACAUGAGCCAAUCCUGGAAGAACCAGCAGAUAGACACCCAAAUCGUAAAGCAAGAGGACAGCUACGGACCAAAAUAGAGUCUGGUGAGGGGACGAUUCCAGUGCGCUCCAAUGCGAGCAUCCAAACGUGGGACGGGGUGCUGCAAGGGGAGCGGCUGCUCACCAUGUCCUGCAGUGACAAGAUUGCACGCUGGAACGUGGUGGGCAUCCAGGGAUCCCUGCUCAGCAUUUUCGUGGAGCCCAUUUACUUCUCGAGCAUCAUCCUGGGCAGCCUUUACCACGGGGACCACCUUUCCAGGGCCAUGUACCAGCGGAUCUCCAACAUAGAGGACCUGCCACCUCUCUACACCCUCAACAAGCCUUUGCUCAGUGGCAUCAGCAAUGCAGAAGCACGGCAGCCAGGGAAGGCCCCCAACUUCAGUGUCAACUGGACGGUAGGCGACUCCGCUAUUGAGGUCAUCAACGCCACGACUGGGAAGGAUGAGCUGGGCCGCGCGUCCCGCCUGUGUAAGCACGCGUUGUACUGUCGCUGGAUGCGUGUGCACGGCAAGGUUCCCUCCCACUUACUACGCUCCAAGAUUACCAAGCCCAACGUGUACCAUGAGUCCAAGCUGGCGGCAAAGGAGUACCAGGCCGCCAAGGUACACUGAGGAGGGGACGGCUCCGUCUUCACAUUGUGCACAGAUCUGAGGAUGGGAUUAGCGAAGCUGUGGAGACUGCACAUCCGGACCUGCCCAUGUCUCAAAACAAACACAUGUACAGUGGCUCUUUUUCCUUCUCAAACACUUUACCCCAGAAGCAGGUGGUCUGCCCCAGGCAUAAAGAAGGAAAAUUGGCCAUCUUUCCCACCUCUAAAUUCUGUAAAAUUAUAGACUUGCUCAAAAGAUUCCUUUUUAUCAUCCCCACGCUGUGUAAGUGGAAAGGGCAUUGUGUUCCGUGUGUGUCCAGUUUACAGCGUCUCUGCCCCCUAGCGUGUUUUGUGACAAUCUCCCUGGGUGAGGAGUGGGUGCACCCAGCCCCGAGGCCAGUGGUUGCUCGGGGCCUUCCGUGUGAGUUCUAGUGUUCACUUGAUGCCGGGGAAUAGAAUUAGAGAAAACUCUGACCUGCCGGGUUCCAGGGACUGGUGGAGGUGGAUGGCAGGUCCGACUCGACCAUGACUUAGUUGUAAGGGUGUGUCGGCUUUUUCAGUCUCAUGUGAAAAUCCUCCUGUCUCUGGCAGCACUGUCUGCACUUUCUUGUUUACUGUUUGAAGGGACGAGUACCAAGCCACAAGAACACUUCUUUUGGCCACAGCAUAAGCUGAUGGUAUGUAAGGAACCGAUGGGCCAUUAAACAUGAACUGAACGGUUAAAAGCACAGUCUAUGGAACGCUAAUGGAGUCAGCCCCUAAAGCUGUUUGCUUUUUCAGGCUUUGGAUUACAUGCUUUUAAUUUGAUUUUAGAAUCUGGACACUUUCUAUGAAUGUAAUUCGGCUGAGAAACAUGUUGCUGAGAUGCAAUCCUCAGUGUUCUCUGUAUGUAAAUCUGUGUAUACACCACACGUUACAACUGCAUGAGCUUCCUCUCGCACAAGACCAGCUGGAACUGAGCAUGAGACGCUGUCAAAUACAGACAAAGGAUUUGAGAUGUUCUCAAUAAAAAGAAAAUGUUUCACUACUC